UUCUGAAAAUGAUCACUAGUGCUUUACAGCUUUUCUUAGAUGACUGCACUAUUUCCUCCGCUUGGAAUUCUCUUUUGGUUAACAGAAACUAGUGCUGAAAAACGGAGCUCAUUUUUUGUCUUCCUGAAAAUAUCUUCACAGAAUUACUUUGCAGAACAUGAUGCAACCUACCUAGAUUCUCUGCCUCUCCCGCUGUGGCUGUGUGAGCGCGAUUGUUGUGUGAAUGACGUUUGAAGAUUCCAAACCUGCUCCACAAAUUACUAAACACAGUCAAGGACUUUAAUCUCAAACCAUAGUGUCAUGAUCACGAGCCACCAAGCCCCUUCCACAAGUUCUUAGGAAGCCAGAUAAGACUAGCAACACAAAAGCUGUUAGCAGGAAGGGCGUUUUAAAGACACAAGCCAUGUUUUGUGCUUCCUCACCUCCCAGAAGGAUUUUCCCUGGAUGAUCCACUAACACACCCUUUCCGAGAUGUUUUCUCAAGGGCCUCCAUUGUCUUCAGCAUCCUCUCAUCUCUUUCCUGUCCCUUUUCCCAGCUGUUGUCACUUCUCCCUCCCAAAGCUCCCAGAUGCCUAGAGAAAACCUUCCAAUUGUGUUCUCCUGGAGAAAGGCCCAAGCUCUGGAACUUUUUUCCGUUUACUCCACUCUCCCUCAGGCUUCAGUUAUCUGCCCAGGGGUUUGGCUGAAAAGAAAGCACGCCUACAUCUGCCUGGCAGCCAUCUGGGCCUAUGCUUCCUUCUGGACCACCAUGCCCUUGAUCAUUGCCAAGGUUAAGUCCUCUUCCAAAGAAGUAGCUCAUUUCGACAGUCGGAUCCAUAGCAGCCAUGUGCUGGAAAUGAAACUGACAAAGGUAGCGAUGUUGAUUUGUGCUGGAUUCCUGAUUGCCUGGAUUCCUUAUGCAGUGGUGUCUGUGUGGUCAGCUUUUGGAAGGCCAGACUCCAUUCCCAUACAGCUCUCUGUGGUGCCAACCCUACUUGCAAAAUCUGCAGCGAUGUACAAUCCCAUCAUUUACCAAGUUAUUGAUUACAAAUUUGCCUGUUGCCAAACUGGUGGUUUGAAAGCAACCAAGAAGAAGUCUCUGGAAGGCUUCAGGCUGCACACCGUAACCACAGUCAGGAAGUCUUCUGCUGUGCUGGAAAUUCAUGAAGAGGACAAAGGGAGAUUAUGGCAUCAGCUAUCUUGUGGGGAGAAUUCUGAGAUGACAGCCUCCAGUGAAACACUAGGGACAAAGGCCCAUUCACCUCUUCAAGAAACCAGGGAAGGGGAAAAUGAAGCUGUUGGUGGGAAUAACAAAUGUUCUGGUUGUGAAGAGUGCAUCUGAAGUGCUUACACGGCGUCUGGCAUAUGCAGAGAAAUUAGCUUACAAAUGUUAUUUUUCUGACUUCUCGCCUCCACUCCACUUACCCUGUCAGGAAAAAAUAAUUCACAAGGAAUAUCAAAACAAUGAUGCACCCUAGGAGUAUCCAAGUAUCUUAACUGAGUUAUCUCAUUCUGGUAUAGUGGCAGAGUUAUAACUAAAGAGUGCCAGAAACCCACGCUUUAAACAUCCUGCAGUGCACACCUCGGUCUCGUCAGUAAGGACUUCACUUUCUUCUGAACUGGGGCUUGUGAAAGCUGGCCUGAAAAGCCUGAUUCAAGGAGAUCAGGCUGUGUCUCUGACUGGAGCAGCUACACUCCCCAUCUGUAAUUUGAUUUGUUCUAUUGCAGAUGAUGUACUGGGCAGAGGUGAGUGUGGAUUGGUGAAAAUCUGUUUUUAUGACUGGCAAAGCAGUGCAGGGGGGUCUUUCACUGAUAAGAAGCAUCAUCAGUAGGGUUUGUCCCUGAUGCCUUUACAACAGCAUCUGAGCACCUCUCAAGUUUUUCCAGGCCAGCUCCAGUUUCAGUGAGGAGAGUGUGGGCUUUCUAUUCCCCAAAUAUUCUUACUACAGUUAAUAUGUAGGUUACUGCCCCAGCCCAACUGCAGGUUCCCAGAUGUGAGUUCCAUGUAGGCAGAAACUGUCCAGUUCUUGAAAUUGAAUUACUUCCUUGUGUAUGUGUUUUUUUCCUACUUAAAGCUCCUCGGGAUGCUUCCUCUCAAAAGUCUUUGAAGAAUAAGAGGUUAAGCUAAGACAACCUGAAUCAAUUUUUUUUUUUUUGUCAAAUGCGAUUGAAAUUAUCCCCAUAAUUCAAUAAAAUAGCUUUUUCCCUUCUUUCUUUUUACUUUGUUGGAAACUAUGCAACAGAAACAAAGUAAGAAGACUCUACCUUAAUUUUAAAGGUAACUCUUACAUAAAGAAGAAAGUCAUUAUGCCAGGCCAGGGGGAGAGUGGAAAGGGGAAAUUUAGAGAAUAGAAACAAACUUAAGCAUCUUGUAAAUUUUGAGUGAAUUGUAAACACAUAAUGAAUGAAUGAGAAGGGCCAGCCAGGAGUCUGUGAAAUGGUCCAGUUGGGAAAUGCCUAAUGCAUAAACACAAAUCUUGGUGACAGGUAGGUUAGUUAUCUGUGAACUUUCUAAAGAUUAAAUAAACAAUAAUAGGAUUUUGUUAAUGUGCCAAAGUGAGUUUAAACCAUGAAAGACACGAUGCAAAUAUGCAAGUACCUUUAAUUGGGCAUAAUAAAAAGUAGUGAGGUAUGGUUAAAAUAACAUUUAGAACAAGAGAGAAGUUAGGGAGAAUUUUUGUCUAAAAAGCCAAAAAGUGAUAGUUGAUUGGUGAUUUUGUUGUUAUCAGGAGAGAGAAUUUUCUUAAUGUAAUAAGUUAGGUACUUUGGCAAGUGAAAUGGGUUCUAGGCCAAUUGCAAGUCCUUAGGAUUCCCUGGCAGCUAGAAACCUUGGCACUCCCAAAAGACAGCUUCAGUUAAAAUGACAGAUGAACAUGAGUCUUCAAGUCAAAACUACUGUUGUACCACGUCCAUUGAAUGUUUGGUGAUUCAAGUCUCUGUUAUUCAAGAACUGAUUCUGUUUUUCCUCCUGUCAAAACCUUGGUUGAUUUUGACUGUAGUAGCACAUCUGGCAGGAAUAUGACAGAAAAAAAUUAAGUUAAAAAUAUAAUUUCUAUUCCCCUAUUUUUUCUGUAAAAGGCUUUAUGGGGAAGAAGGGAAGAAGGUUGACAUGAGUAGAGAUGAUACUUGCCUCUGGAUGACCCAGUUGGGUUCUCCUUUGACUGCCAUUCACCACAGUUGACCUCAUUAGGCUCCGAAGUAUGAGAAGAGCUUCAUUGCCAAGUUAGUGAAAGAAGCAGAUGAUUUACUUUUGCUCGAGUGGGUCUGUAGACCUCGGGAGGUUAGCCAUUUCUCUUAGAGUUUGGUGUAUGUAUUAAGAUACAGCAUGUAUGUAGGUAUAUAUAAUACAUAUAUGUGUGUAUACAUAUAUAUAUAUUUCUGGUUUGUUUAAUAUCUUUUAAAAAAUUUUAAUGGAAUUUUUUGAACAUGUACAAAAGAGAAAGAAUCCUACGAUGAACUCCCAUGUAUCCAUCAUCCAGCCUCAAUAGUGAUCAACCCAUAGCAUAUUGUGGUUCAUGUUGACACUCAUCCACCUCUUUCCUUCCCCAUCUCUCCCCAUUAUUUUGAGACGAAUGAGAUCCUGGGAUUUCGUGAAAAUAUUAUGAAUAUCUUAUUUGUGAGAACAAGAUUUCCCAAAGCAUGAUCCCCAGAAACCUAGUCCUGCAAAACUACUGCAAAAAUAAAGUGUUCUAAUCUCCAAA